CUCUCCCCAGUUCAGUGGCUCAAGGUGCCAAAGCAAGGUGCUCAAGGUGUCACUUGGUCACAAGCCCUCCAACUGGACAACUGCGGGGCACCAGGGGAAACCUGCCUGAUAUCCCAGUGCCACUGGAAGAAACGGACCUAGCCAGGACGGCGAGGGGGACACGAGGAAAGACUAGUCGAGAGACAGACCCCCCCCGGAAUUCUGAGCACCAAAAGCAGAUCCCUCUUAGAAGGAAGUGUUACCAUUUCCUUGUUACAGCUGAGGAAACUGAGGCAUGGAGCCAAAGACAGAGCCUGACACAAUAGAUGCUCAGUAUAUUGGAUUGAAUUGGAGGGAAAACGUUCAAUGGGCCACCAUCUACACCCUGGACGGCUGGGUGUUCGGCUCGCUGCUGUGCAAGGCGGUGCACUUCCUCAUCUUCCUCACCAUGCACGCCAGCAGCUUCACGCUGGCCGCCGUCUCCCUGGACAGGUAUCUGGCCAUCCGCUACCCGCUGCACUCCCGCGAGCUGCGCACGCCUCGAAACGCGCUGGCAGCCAUCGGGCUCAUCUGGGGGCUGUCGCUGCUCUUCUCCGGGCCCUACCUGAGCUACUACCGCCAGUCGCAGCUGGCCAACCUGACCGUGUGCCAUCCCGCGUGGAGCGCCCCUCGCCGCCGCGCCAUGGACAUCUGCACCUUCGUCUUCAGCUACCUGCUUCCUGUGCUGGUUCUCGGCCUGACCUACGCGCGCACCUUGCGCUACCUCUGGCGCGCCGUCGACCCGGUGGCCGCGGGCUCGGGUGCCCGGCGCGCCAAGCGCAAGGUGACACGCAUGAUCCUCAUCGUGGCCGCGCUCUUCUGCCUCUGCUGGAUGCCCCACCACGCGCUCAUCCUCUGCGUGUGGUUCGGCCAGUUCCCGCUCACGCGCGCCACUUAUGCGCUUCGCAUCCUCUCGCACCUGGUCUCCUACGCCAACUCCUGCGUCAACCCCAUCGUUUACGCGCUGGUCUCCAAGCACUUCCGCAAAGGCUUCCGCACGAUCUGCGCGGGCCUGCUGGGCCGUGCCCCAGGCCGAGCCUCGGGCCGUGUGUGCGCUGCCGCGCGGGGCACCCACAGUGGCAGCGUGUUGGAGCGCGAGUCCAGCGACCUGUUGCACAUGAGCGAGGCGGCGGGGGCCCUUCGUCCCUGCCCCGGCGCUUCCCAGCCAUGCAUCCUCGAGCCCUGUCCUGGCCCGUCCUGGCAGGGCCCAAAGGCAGGCGACAGCAUCCUGACGGUUGAUGUGGCCUGAAAGCACUUAGCGGGCGCGCUGGGAUGUCACAGAGUUGGAGUCAUUGUUGGGGGACCGUGGGGAGAGCUUUGCCUGUUAAUAAAACGCACAAACCAUUUCACACACA